AAACCCAUUCAAAGGCUCCCCUUUGCACUUUAGAUAAAACCCAUUUUCCAUAUGCUGCUUUCCAGCUCCAGCAGGACACUCGUGUCUUCUCUUGCCUCACUUCCAGCCACUCACACCCUUGCCCACUCUUCCUUGGCCACAGUUUUUCCUCCAGUUACCCAAAUGCAUGGAAUUCUCUCCACCCCUGUGCCACCCUCUUGGCAUUUUUCUCUGGAGGUCUCACUCUACAGCCCCUGGAGUGGCCGCACUUUCUCGUCCUCUUGAUCUCAUUGUCACCUCCUCAAGGGGUCUUCACCAGAAGUCCAAGCAGGUCCCUGGCCCCACAAUCAUGUUUGUUCCUGCAUAAGAUUUCAUGGCUUGUUAAUAUUUACAUGUUUCAUAUCCAGACAGUUUCUAAGCCCUGUAAGGGCAAGGGCCAUGUCUGCUUUGCUCCCCACUGGGCAGGGCCUGACACAUGAUAGGCAUUCAUAUCAGGGCCAUUUGCUGAGAUAUGUGAAUGAGUGAAUGGAGGCUGACAUGCAGCUCAGCUCGGAUUUGUCCUUUCCUUUAGGAGACAGAGCCAACCUCUCUGUUGUGCUUCAUGCCCCUUUAGAGCCACAACGUUUUGGAGAUUGAGGAGAUCUUGGAGGGCUUCUCUCUCACAUAUCCGCCAUUUGGGCUCCAUCUCCCAUCCUCCUGCAUUUCAGUACAGCUCAGGCCCAGCCUUGGAUUCAGGGGGUCUUUUGCUGUCCGUCUCGCCUUGUCAGGGGACGCACCCAUGUGGCUUUCCUCCCAUGUCCUUUGGGAGCGGGAUUAUGGUGCAGUGGUUUAGGAUGUAUGGAGCCAAACUGCAGGGGUCUGAAUCCUGGCUUACUAGUGGUGUGACCUUUACAAGAUACUUAAUCUCUGUGUUCCUUGGUUUCCUCACAUGUCAAGUGGGGUUAAUGAGCACAUGCAGCUGUGACAGUGAUUCGGUGAGUAAAUGUACUUAAGGCACUUAUCAUGAAGAUAGUCAAUAUGCGUUGGCCAUCUGCCUCUCUCCCCUCUACGUUCUUCUUAUGAUCUCCAUGCACUGUAAUCCUUCCAGGCUCUUCCCAGUACCCGCAUAGUGAGAACAGUCAGCUACUCUCUACAGUCUCUUUAGCUUAGUCCUCUUCUUACUCUUACUUUCUCCUUUUCCCCCUUUUUCUAAUUCAGUGUUGUUGUUUUUUUAACCUUUUUGGGGUCACAGGCUCUUUUGAGAAUUUAAAGAAGAAUACCUAUGGACUGUUGCCUUAGAAAAACUCAGUAUUUGUGCAAUCACCCAAAAUGAGCAUACAAUUCAAAUGUCCACAGAUGCCUUGGAAUCUCUCUACGGCCCCCUAGAUAGAGCUCCCCUGUCUCUGUUGUCUUCUUUGGUGCUGUGGACCAAAGGUAUUCCACCCAGAAAACUAGAACUGACCCUUCAUGGAUAUUUAGGAAACCUCAGAAUACAGCUAGAAAAGUCUCCUUCCAGAAGGUGAAAUUAUGAUACCAUUUCUAUGUGUAUCCAACUGCAUGGUACUAAACGGGUAUAUGCAUAAAGUGAUUAUGUCUUAUAAUACAGCUUAUGAUUGCUACUCAUUUGGGACAUAUGGGAAUGCCAGGCUACUUUAAGUGAGGACAAAUUUGAAUUAAAUAUACGUGUGUGUGUGUGUGUGUGUUUUAAGCCCAGUUUCUUCUCAAGUUGUACGGUAAUAAGACAUGAUAUAUGUGUGCCAAUGGUGAUAAUAACAGCCAGCUGUUUUCUAGAUAGAAGUCCUUUUGGACAUAGUUUUAUACUUGUGUGUAAAGUAUAAAUAAGUUAUUAUAAAGUAAAAUAAGCAUUUAUUAUGGCUGUAUUAAUUACCAGUGUACAAAAAGUGCUGCAGAAAUAGUCUAGAUAACAAUAUGUUUCUUGGAGGGGAUUAAAUGUUCCUUCAGCAAAUGUGUUCACUUUCUAAAUUGGUUAGUAAACUGUCUUAUAGAUACCAAGGUAUACUUAAUGCUGGUCAUGGAUUAGCGGGUCAAAAUUGAUAAGUUUGAAAAAUUAAAAGACAAAAACAAAUAAGGAAAUCAUGAUGUUUUAUCGGGGUGAUUGUUUCUGGACUAGGCCCUCGCAGAACAAACAAGUGCUCCCUGACCCCCUGGGCUGAGCGCAUUGUGCACCCUGGUAGGUGAUGGAGGCCUUGGCCACAUUGACCCAAAAGCAGUGCCCGUGAAGGAUUGCUCAAAGGUUCCAUGUGCCCAGGGCUUAGGAAUGCUCCAUCUCAAACGGUGUUUUUAAAAUUGUAUUUUCUUCAGGAUUAAAAUCACCAACUGAACCUUCCAAGGAGACCAACUGAGUGGAAAUCAUCUUCAGUAACUGCUAAUGGGAGCUGGAUUUAAAACCGUCAACUUAAAAGUUGGCCACCCUGUUCAAGGGCUUAGGAGAAAGUCAACACACUUCGCAACUUGAAUUGGUCCCAGCUGCUCCCAGAAGAACGGGCGGGUUGGUCCCUAUGCCACCCCUGGAGAGCUACUCGCCGCCCACUUUGCCGUGAAGGGCUGUGCGGUUCCCGUGCGCGCCGGAGCCUGCUGUGGCCUCUUAUGCACUCCACCACCCCCAUCAGCUCCCUCUUCUCCUUCACCAGCCCCGCAGUGAAGAGACUGCUAGGCUGGAAGCAAGGAGAUGAAGAGGAAAAGUGGGCAGAGAAGGCAGUGGACUCUCUAGUGAAGAAGUUAAAGAAGAAGAAGGGAGCCAUGGACGAGCUGGAGAGGGCUCUCAGCUGCCCGGGGCAGCCCAGCAAAUGCGUCACGAUUCCCCGCUCCCUGGACGGGCGGCUGCAGGUGUCCCACCGCAAGGGCCUGCCCCAUGUGAUUUACUGUCGCGUGUGGCGCUGGCCGGAUCUGCAGUCCCACCACGAGCUGAAGCCGCUGGAGUGCUGUGAGUUCCCAUUUGGCUCCAAGCAGAAAGAAGUGUGCAUUAACCCUUACCACUACCGCCGGGUGGAGACUCCAGUACUGCCUCCUGUGCUCGUGCCAAGACACAGUGAAUAUAACCCCCAGCUCAGCCUCCUGGCCAAGUUCCGCAGCGCCUCCCUGCACAGUGAGCCACUCAUGCCACACAACGCCACCUAUCCUGACUCUUUCCAGCAGCCUCCGUGCUCUGCACUCCCUCCCUCACCCAGCCACGCGUUCUCCCAGUCCCCGUGCACGGCCAGCUACCCUCACUCCCCAGGAAGUCCUUCUGAGCCAGAGAGUCCCUAUCAACACUCAGUUGACACACCACCCCUGCCUUAUCAUGCCACAGAAGCCUCUGAGACCCAGAGUGGCCAACCUGUAGAUGCCACAGCUGAUAGACAUGUAGUGCUAUCGAUACCAAAUGGAGACUUUCGACCAGUUUGUUACGAGGAGCCCCAGCACUGGUGCUCGGUCGCCUACUAUGAACUGAACAACCGAGUUGGGGAGACAUUCCAGGCUUCCUCCCGAAGUGUGCUCAUAGAUGGGUUCACCGACCCUUCAAAUAACAGGAACAGAUUCUGUCUUGGACUUCUUUCUAAUGUAAACAGAAACUCAACGAUAGAAAAUACCAGGAGACAUAUAGGAAAGGGUGUGCACUUGUACUACGUCGGGGGAGAGGUGUAUGCCGAGUGCGUGAGUGACAGCAGCAUCUUUGUGCAGAGCCGGAACUGCAACUAUCAACACGGCUUCCACCCAGCUACCGUCUGCAAGAUCCCCAGCGGCUGCAGCCUCAAGGUCUUCAACAACCAGCUCUUCGCUCAGCUCCUGGCCCAGUCAGUUCACCACGGCUUUGAAGUCGUGUAUGAACUGACCAAGAUGUGUACUAUCCGGAUGAGUUUUGUUAAGGUUGCUAUGAAGGCUGGAGAACCAAGGAAGUUUCUUAGUGGGAAGGAAAGACAACUGGGUUUGUAUAUGGAAGUGAAAGCCUUCAGUUUCAUCACCUGCUAUUUUGUCUGUUGCAAAGUACUCGCAAAUGAGUCUAGUAUUUCAAAAUAUGGGCUUAUCAAAGUAUCGGGGUAUGUGUGACAGUUUUCUUACUGCCAUGAUUCCAUCCAGGGAAUCAGCAUGGCUUGUUCCAGGCAUUUUUUUCAAAGUAAAUUUUAUUAGCACUUUAAAAUUACCAUGACAAAUAAUUUUUCUAUACUCAAAUUAUGUUUUUAUUAUCACUUUAGUAAUUAUUUAAAAAGUAAGAACAAUAUAGUUUCCAAUUUUAAAAAACAGCUGCUUGAAAUUAUUUCUCUUUCAUGGUGACAAAGCAGUUUCAUUCAAAUUUAGUGUUUUGAAAGCAUAUAUUAUAAAGUUAUAUUAACAAAUAACUUCGAAAUCUUUUCAAAUGUUCUGUUGCUUUAGAAACGGCAGAGGGCAUCAUUUGAAUCAUACAGUUUUUUUUUUUUCCGGGUCUGUGUUUUUAAAAUUAGGAUGAAAUGCCAAUAUCUCAUAGGUAAUUAUUUCACUCUGAUUAAAUAUAAGCUUAUAUAGAAAUCUGAUUUUCCUAAUAACUAGAUACAUUUCUCAGAUAGGCAGCAUUUACAUUCAUAAAGCUACACAAUUGACACAGAAGACAAACUGUUCCUAAUACUGCAGGAACUUUUAAAAUAAAUACAUAGUAAAUAUAACUAUAGAUCAUUUUUUUUUAACAUUUGAGAUGAGCAGCUGUAGCUACCACUGGGCUGAUGGAUCAGAUCUCUUUAAGGUUUCUUUCAGCUCUGAUUUUUACUGAUUCUAGGACUUAGUCAGUCAACAAAUGUUUAUUGAGCACCUGCCAUGUGCAGGCCAGGCACGUGGGACAUGCCAAUGUUUACUCACAGAUCUCUGACCUCAGGGAACCAAUAUUCUAGGAAGGAGAGAUGGAUAAUAAACAACAGCCAAAACACAGAAGAAGGAUGGAAAGAGAAAGUCUGGGGGCAGGGUGAAGGGAAUUGGAGCACGGGGGCAGUGGAGUCAUCUGCACAUGAGGGUGGGCCUCAUUGAAAAGGUGACAGGUCAGCAGAGACUGGAAGGAGACAUGGAGCUAGGCCCAGGGACCCCUGGAGGAAGAGCAGAAGAAGAGGGAAGAGCAAGGCAACAGCAUACACCUGGAAACUCUGAAGAGCAGGCAGGCCAGUGUGGCUGGGGCCUAAUGAGCAGGGGAAGUGAGAUGAGAGCAGCCGCAGGGAACCAUAGCAAGGCCUCCUGAACCUCUGCUACGAGUUCAGCGGUGACUGUAAGGAGGUGGCGAGCUUUUGCAGGGAUCAGAGCAGAGCAUUUUCAUGAUCUAACUUCUAUUCUUAAAGGAUCGCCCUGCCUGCUGUGUGGAGGAUAGAUAUUAUACAGGCAAGGUUGCAAGUAGGGAAACCACUUAGGAGGCUAUAGUAAUAGUCAGGUGAGAGUCGCCCCCACCUGGAGGGAUCCAGUACAGCUGUGAGAAGUGGAAGGAUUCUGAAUUGUGAAGGCGGAUCAGGCGUGGGAGAAAAAGAGGAAGAUGAAGUUAGUUGCCUUCAAUCAAGAUGGAGAAGACGCAGGUGUAAUUGAGAUGUCCGUUGCAUUCAAGUGGAGUUGCUGAGUAGCCAGUUCGAUAUAAGAGUCUGGAUUCGGGGAGAGAGGUUUGGGCUUGAAAUACAAAUUUGGGAAUUGUCUGCAAAGGGACCGUAUUUAACUCCCUAAGUGUGGAUGAGAACACCAAAGGUUUGAGUUUAAACUGAGAAGAGCCGGGCGUGGUGGCUCAUGCCUGUAAUCCCAGCACUUUGGGAGGCUAAGGUGGGUGGAUUGCUUGAGGUCAGGAGUUCAAGACUAGCCUGGCCAACAUGGCAAAACCCCAUCUCUACUAAAAAUACAAAAAUUAGCCAGGCGUGGUGGCGCGUGCCUGUAAUCUCAGCACUUGGGAGGCUUAGGCAGGAGAAUCGCUUGAACCUCGGAGGCAGAGGUUGCAGUGAGCUGAGAUCGCACCAUUGCACUCCAGCCUGGGUGACAGAGCCAGACUCCAUCUCAAAAAAAUUAAAAUAAAUAAAUAAGAAAGGGGGCUCUAGGACUGAGCCCUGGGACACUUCAACAUUUAAAGAUGGGACAGAAGGGACAGAAUCAGCAAAGAAAACUGAGAAAGACCAACCAGUGAGGUAGUAAUAAGACCAAGAAGUGUGGUGCUUUGGAAGCCGAGAAAAGACAGUGCAUUGAUGAGAGGAUGUGAUGAACUAAAUCAAAUGCUGCCCACAUAACACAAAGGCUGAGAGCUGAUCAUUCAUUUUAACAAUAUGAAGGCCUUUUUUGAUCUUGACAAGAAAAGUUUUGUUGGCGGCUGGGGUGAGAUGAUGAUCAGAAUGGAUUUAAGAGAGAAUGGAAGGAGACAAAUUGAGAUGGCUAGUAUGGAUGACUCUUCUGAGGGUUUUUGCCAGAAAUGGGAUAAAAACAUAGGGCAGUAGCUGGUGGGGGGUGGAGAAGUAUCUUGAAGGUGGAAGACAUUUCAGUGUGUUCAUAUGUUGACGGGAAUGAUAUAGUAGACGCAAAAGAUUGCAGGAGAGAAGGGGAAGAUUUGCUGGAAUGAUGUCUCUGGGAAGGCAGGUCUGAGAGUGCAUUAAUGGGUGGACCAGCUUAUUUGGAAACACAAAUAAUUAAUCUGUGGUAAGAGGUAGAAAGGCCAAGUAUGUGGAUGCAGGUCCUGUGGAAACUUAUUUCUGAUGUAUUCAUUUUUCUCAUUAAAAUACAAAAUAAAUAUCAGUUGCAGGUAUGGACAGGGAAAAAGGGGUUGCAGGUUUUAGUGGGGAGGAGCGAUCACCUAGGAGGGGGACAUGAGAGAAGGGACUGGGGGGUGGGUUGUGACUGCCGGGGACAUCACAGGUCCACUUGAGGUUCUCAGUCAUGAAAGUAAAAUGUGAUCAGGCAGCAUGGUUGUGUUGAAAUCCAAGUUUUAAAAAACUCUACAGAGAAUCACUGCUCCCAGUCACAGAACUGAUUUACUUGGCUGUGAUCUCCCUUCAUUUUUAAAUAUCCUUUCAUUGAUAUAUAACAUAUAGAGAAAAAUAUGCAAAUUAAAAAAAAAAAUUUUAACUGUCUCUCCUUUGAAUGGUGAUAAAAGGGAAAUUGCCAGUUGAACUAGAGAGAGAGAGAGAGAGAGAAUAAGCAAGCUUUGAUAAUGAGCCCUGAAAAACCAAGAGCGCCUUCCAGUUCUGUCUUUACCACUUUCAGGUCCAGUCACUGGUCUGCAGUAACCAUUUUGUGCAAGACACUGUCCUGGGCAUGAAGGGGUGAACAAAAGGUCAAGUUUCUUCCUUUGUGGAAGGGAAAAUGAUUUUUCAGUGCUUCCCGUGUGACUGGAGUGCCAGAACCUCUCUAGAUCCGAGUAUUCAGUUGUGAACCCUGAGGGAAUGCACUGAUUUGGAUUCAUCUGAAGGCAUCUGGUUGGUGUGAGAGUUGACCUGUGUUUACAGGAAGGUAGAGGCCAUGUUCUCUCCCUCUCAGGUCUCAGGAGCUACGCUGGGGUGUGGGCUCUGUGCCCCGCUGAGCUCUGCCUGGGGCUCUGGAGGCUGAGUGUAAGUGUGGCACCAUCACUCAGCUCCUUUCUUGUUUUUCAGGGUUGGGGUGCUGAGUAUCAUCGCCAGGAUGUCACCAGCACCCCCUGCUGGAUUGAGAUUCAUCUUCAUGGGCCACUGCAGUGGCUGGACAAAGUUCUGACUCAGAUGGGCUCUCCACAUAACCCCAUUUCUUCAGUGUCUUAACAGUCAUGUCUUAAGCUGCAUUUCCAUAGGAUAGAGGCUAUUGCAGGGAGUGGCUUGUAUCAUUUCAGAUUUGCAACUGAAGUUUCUAAAAACAUGUGUAAAUACAUAGAAUGUAUACUGUUCUUAUUUUUUUUAAUCACCGUUUGUUUUGUGCUUUCUAGUUAACCUGAUGCCAGUACAGUGCAAUUGGAAAAGCAGGACUUUGGUGCCUGUGCUAUAAGCAGCAGAUUUUGUGGGAGGAAACACUUGAGAGGCGAUAUUGUCAACAGUAUUUGAAGGGUGUUAGCAGAAUAAAAGACAGCUUUAGUCAGCCGUGUCAUUAUAAAGCAUGUUGUGUGGCCUCACAGAAACAUUGAAACUGUUUAUACAGCAAAAGUCAGGUAUUAGCAGCACUAAAGCAAAUAUCACUCAGAUGAAACAAAGCAGUGAAACCCCUACAGUUUAAAUGAUGUCACUUUUAGUGCUGUUGGCAAGAAAAAAAAAACAACAAACUUGUACAAUGAAUUAAUGAGAUAGGCCAUAGAAACUUUAUUUCUAAGGUUGACAUACCUAUAGCUGGGCUCCUGUGCUCAUAUUCAGUGGUACAUUUUAAACAAACUGUGAUCGGAAAAGAAAAAAAACUGUGAAGCCAAAAGUCAUGUUCCCUCAGUCUACCACUGUAAAAACAGAGUCUAAUAUGGGAAAAUAAAUAUGAAAAUAGCAUGAAAUGCUGUUUCCCAGAUUGCAAGAUAAGACCAGAACUUGGUCCAAGAGCCAGCCACCCAGGGAGACUCCUGCUUUCCACAGAGGAGACCAGGUUCCUGUCGUGCUGGUUGUUCGUGUCAGGCAGUCCUGCAAACUUUGAGUCUGCGCAGCGUGCCAGAAUAGCUUGUGUUUCAGUCCUGUGUCAAGAAGCAGGUGAAACCAAAGGUUGGAGAAAAGCAUCACACGUCGACUUACACUUUCUCAUUUCCCACGUUCCAGUCUCCUGGGAAGGGCACUCUUUCGCCACGUUUUCCUGCCUCUUGGCAAAUAUUAACUCUUUGCAGAUCACUAAAGCAACAGUAAAGACUUUGAGAAAAUCUAGACACAUUAUUGGAUCAAUGAGUUAUUUAACCUAGUGUCUAGUGAUUAUCUAACCUGGAAAUAAAUUCCCAAGGAAAGUGAUAAUAAUUUCAUAAUCAUCUGCAAUUUCUGGGGAACAGUGGUACUGAAUAAUAAGACAUCUUUUAAAAAUAUACACAAUAUUAAAAACCUGUUCUUAUUUUACUUUAGAUGAGGGAGGAAAAUCCCCCAAAUUUCUAGGUACUUUCAUAUAUAUACUUGCCAUGCACUAAACACUGCAUUGCUUGGAAAAAUAUUUCACACCCUCUUUAAAAAUGUACAAUUUAAGAUGGCAGUUAUGCUUGUAACAGACAGCACUUCAGUAAUCCAAGAAGUUUCUUCAUUUAUACAUUUUAUCUCAACUCUUUCUAGCAUUAGUGCACAUGGUAGUUUUUCUAAUUAAAUUGUAUUCAAGGUAGAAAUGAUCAUGUGAGAAAGAUAUAUGAUUGAGCUACUACUGUCACCUCUUACAGUUACUAGUGUUAGCUAAUAGAAACUUUCAUAUAUACACAUAGAAAAGAAUUAUUACAUUUUACAUUGAAAAAUGUAAUAUAUGGCCCAUGUAGUGUAUAGAAAAAUCUGUAGUUUAUUGGUUCAUCAACUAUGUAUUGUGCACCUACCUAUGGGUGUCAGGUACAAUGUUAGGUACUGUAGAAUCAAAUGUAAAUAAGAGACAGUCCCAGCCCUCAGGGAGCCGAGAACCUAAUAGUGAAUCUGUUUGUACAGACAUCUUCAUGUUUCAGAACUUUUAAAACAAAACAAAAUAAUGUAAUCUAUCAUCUUUUGCUUGAAAGAAUGUGAUUGAUUUCUUAUCUCUGUUUUGAAAUUAUUUCCUUACUCUUCUGCAAAGUCAGGUAAUGGAUUCCUUGUAUAAAUGCUACUUUUCUUCCAUGUCUCAAAGUUGUUUUUUUUCCUCCCCUUUCUUCCCUGUUUUCCAAUAAUUCUCCAUGUCCCCUUUUCUUAGAAAAGGCAUUAAUAUGGUGAAUCUUGUAUGGGAACCAUUCCAUGGGAGAACUUCAACACAGUUUUUGCUCCAGAGAUCAAACAUAGCUUUCGUGAUCUCUCUACCAGCUAUCUAACUUAUCCUCUGGUAAUCUUUUUUUUUUUUUUUUUUUUUUUGAGAUGGAGUCUCGCUGUGUCACCAGGCCAGAGUGCAGUGGCGUGAUCUUGGCUCACUGCAACCUCUGCCUCCCGGGUUCGAGUGAUUCUCCUGCCUCAGCCUCCCAAGUAGUUGGGACUACAGGCUACCACGCCCAGCUAAUUUUUAUAUUUUUAGUAGAGACGGGGUUUCACCAUGGUAGCCAGAAUGGUCUCUAUCUCUUGACCUUGUGAUCCGCCCGCCUCAGCCUCCCAAAGUGCUGGGAUUACAGGCGUGAGCCACUGCGCCCGGCUUCCUCUGGUAAUCUUACACCUUUACAGAAUUAAUCUAAACUGGUGGCUCAUAAAUGACAUUAAAAACAAAAAAAAAAUCUGGAUGCAGUGGCUCAUUCCUAUAGUCCCAGCACUUUGGGAGGCCAAGGCGGGAGGAUCAUCUGAGCCCAGGAGUUUGGGGCUGUAGUGAACUAUGAUCAUACAACUUCAUUCUAGCCUGGGUGACAAAGUGACACCCUGUCUCUAAACAAAAAUCAAGAAACAAAAAACUUGUAUUUCCCUGCAGCUUUGGGAAGCCAGAACACAAUAUUGCAGUGAAUCUGAAUUUUCUGUGACAAAUAAAUUAUUAAAUUGGCACAUAUGAUCAUCACCAGUCAUGUCUCAUCAAAAGCCUUUAUUAUGAUGCUUGUACAUUUUGAAGAAUUUAGAAUUAAUGAGAAGUUAACCCUUUAGUCAUUGUAACACAAUCAUAUUUUAAUCAGCUUUUUCUUUUGCUACCAAGAGUUUCAAAAAAUAAAUGCAGUAUUUGAUUUCAGGCUGCUAAAUGGGCUCAUUUAGCAUUCAUUCCUUGAUGUAGACAUUAAAAAAAAAACUGAAUAGCAUUCUUUCCAGGAUAACUAAUAAAGCAGACAUGCUAAGCCUAUAAAUACAUCAGCACUGCAGCACACGUUUAAGGUUGCCACGGACAAGGAUCACACAAUAGAGAACACUGUAGUAACAUUUCGGUCUGCUCACAAGACCCAGAACAUUGAUCAGUUUUUGUUGUUGGUUUAUUAUUUUUCUGUUAAAAAAUUGUGAAAAGUUUGUUUUAGCUAGAUGAUAUUUUAAUAGCUGCGAGUGCUUUGGAACUAUAAAGAUGUCACUACUUAACACAUAUACCUUAUGUUUUGUUUUGUUUUGUUUUACACUCAGUAUAAAUCAGGAGAAGUUAGCCAACCAUCUAGCAUUUAGAAUCCUCUUUUUUAUUGUCUUCUAAGGAUAUGGAUGUUCCCAUAACAGCAACAAAACAGCAACAAAAACAUUUCAUAAAUAUCACUUGAUAGACUGUAAGCACCUGCUUAACUUUGUGUCCCAAAUAUUUAGUGUGUAUAUAUAUAUAUAUAUAUACACACACACACACAUAUAUAUUCAACAAAUAAAGCAAAAUAUAACAUGCAUUUCACAUUUUGUCUUUCCCUGUUACGAUUUUAAUAGCAGAACUGUAUGACAAGUUUAGGUGAUCCUAGCAUAUGUUAAAUUCAAAUUAAUGUAAAACAGAUUAACAACAACAAAGAAACUGUCUAUUUGAGUGAAGUCAUGCUUUCUAUUAUAAUAACUUGGCUUCGGUUAUCCAUCAAAUGCACACUUAUACUGUUAUCUGAUUGUUUAUAAUAAAGAAUACUGUACUUAUA